GAGACAGGCGUCCAGGGCGCCUGGGGAACCGGCACGGCGGAGCAGCGGCGGCGGGGCUGGGGGGAGGCCGCCGAGUCGGCCGCGGCCGAGGAGGGGCAGGCGGAGGUCGGGGGCGCCGCGGCCGCGGGGUCAGGUUCCCCGGCGGGAGGCGCAGGUGGCGGCCUGGGGAGCUGGCGGCCGCUCCUCGCCUGGCUGCAGCGGCGGCAGCCCCAGUGCUGCCCCUGUGCGGCGCCCCUUUCCCGCUCCGCCGCGCACUGUUGUCAUGGAGGAACCAAGAUGGCGGCUCUGGCCUACAACCUGGGCAAGCGGGAGAUCAACCACUACUUCAGCGUGAGGAGCGCCAAGGUGCUGGCGCUGGUGGCCGUGCUGCUGCUCGCAGCGUGCCACCUCGCCUCCCGCCGCUACCGAGGCAAUGAUUCGUGUGAAUACCUUCUCUCAAGUGGCAGAUUUCUUGGAGAGAAAGUUUGGCAACCUCACAGUUGUAUGAUGCAUAAAUACAAAAUCAGUGAAGCAAAGAACUGCCUUGUAGAUAAACAUAUUGCAUUUAUUGGAGAUUCCAGAAUUCGUCAAUUGUUUUAUUCUUUUGUAAAAAUAAUUAAUCCCCAAUUCAAAGAAGAAGGAAAUAAGCAUGAAAACAUUCCUUUUGAAGACAAGACUGCAUCAGUUAAAGUGGAUUUUCUGUGGCAUCCUGAAGUUAAUGGUUCUAUGAAACAGUGUAUCAAAGUGUGGACUGAGGAUUCCAUUGCAAAGCCACAUGUGAUUGUAGCAGGAGCUGCCACAUGGUCCAUCAAGAUUCACAAUGGUAGCAGUGAAGCGCUUUCUCAAUAUAAAAUGAACAUCACCUCCAUAGCACCACUUUUAGAAAAAUUGGCAAAGACUAGUGAUGUUUAUUGGGUCUUACAAGAUCCUGUUUAUGAAGAUCUAUUAAGUGAAAAUAGGAAGAUGAUCACUAAUGAGAAGAUAGAUGCUUACAAUGAAGCUGCAGUCAGUAUUUUGAAUAGUAGCACCAGAAAUUCUAAAUCAAAUGUUAAGAUGUUCAGUGUUUCCAAAUUAAUUGCUCAAGAAACCAUCAUGGAAUCUUUGGAUGGCUUACAUCUUCCUGAAUCGAGCAGAGAAACUACUGCAAUGAUUCUUAUGAAUGUGUAUUGCAAUAAGAUUUUGAAGCCUGUAGAUGGGUCCUGUUGUCAACCUCGGCCUCCUGUUACUCUCAUACAGAAGCUAGCUGCUUGUUUUUUCACUUUAUCUAUUAUCGGAUAUUUAAUUUUUUACAUAAUUCAUCGUAAUGCUCAUCGGAAGAAUAAGCCGUGUACUGAUUUGGAAAGUGGAGAGGAAAAGAAAAAUAUUAUCAAUACCCCUGUGUCUUCAUUAGAAAUACUUUUACAAUCUUUCUGCAAACUUGGCCUGAUUAUGGCAUAUUUCUAUAUGUGUGACCGUGCAAAUCUGUUCAUGAAGGAAAACAAAUUUUAUACACAUUCAUCUUUCUUUAUUCCAAUUAUCUACAUUUUGGUUUUGGGAGUAUUUUAUAAUGAAAAUACUAAAGAGACUAAAGUAUUAAAUAGAGAACAAACAGACGAAUGGAAAGGCUGGAUGCAACUUGUGAUUUUGAUUUAUCACAUUUCUGGAGCAAGUACAUUUUUGCCUGUAUACAUGCACAUUCGAGUUCUGGUUGCUGCAUAUUUAUUUCAGACAGGGUAUGGGCAUUUCUCAUACUUUUGGAUAAAAGGAGAUUUUGGAAUCUAUAGAGUAUGUCAGGUUUUAUUUCGUCUCAAUUUCCUGGUAGUGGUGUUAUGUAUAGUAAUGGAUCGACCUUAUCAAUUCUAUUACUUUGUCCCCUUGGUCACUGUAUGGUUCAUGGUCAUAUAUGUUACUUUAGCACUAUGGCCACAAAUAAUCCAAAAAAAAGCAAACGGAAAUUGUUUCUGGCAUUUUGGCUUACUGUUGAAACUAGGCUUUUUGCUGUUAUUCAUAUGUUUUUUGGCAUAUUCUCAGGGUGCAUUUGAGAAGAUCUUUUCUCUUUGGCCAUUGUCCAAGUGUUUUGAACUGAAAGGGAAUGUAUAUGAAUGGUGGUUCAGAUGGAGGUUAGACCGUUAUGUAGUUUUCCACGGAAUGCUGUUUGCUUUUAUUUAUCUGGCUUUGCAGAAGCGUCAAAUACUUUCUGAAGGAAAGGGUGAACCUCUUUUUUCAAACAAAAUUUCAAAUUUUCUGUUGUUUAUUUCAGUAGUUUCUUUCUUGACCUAUUCCAUCUGGGCUAGCAGUUGUAAAAACAAAGCAGAGUGCAAUGAACUCCAUCCGUCUGUUUCUGUGGUACAGAUUUUAGCCUUCAUCCUAAUAAGAAACAUCCCUGGAUAUGCCCGUUCAGUUUACAGUUCAUUUUUUGCUUGGUUUGGAAAAAUUUCAUUAGAGUUUGAUACCACAAUGUACCCUGAAUGUGAGGUGCUAUGGGGAAUAUGAAGAUGAAAGAGACCCUGCCACUGCUUUCCAGGAGUUCACCAUCUGGUAUGGGAGACCAACAUCCACCUAACUAGGUAUUAUCCCAGAGGUAAAACUGCUUUGGCAACACCUGGAAAUAUGGGAGGAGCAAUUAAGGUUGGACAGAUUCAGAAAAGAUUUAUGGAAGAAGUGGAAUUCAAUAUGGCUCUUAAAAUACUACAGUAGUAGGAUUCUGAAACUCAGAGAUGUGGAAUUUCAGCAUUUCACAGUGAACAUAUGUGCAAGAUACAAUACUGGAUACUGUGGGGGCCUUUCGGGGAAGGGAAUUAAGUCAGUAAUGCUGGAUCCUGGGGUAAAUUUAAGGUAGGGGGAGGCAAAACUGGGAAGAAAAGAAGAGUUAAAAUAGGGAGUUUUGAACUCCUGCUAAAAAGUCAUUUCACUCUGUAUAUCAAAGUAUUUAAAUUCAGGAUCACAACCCUACAUCCAAAGCAGAGAACAUUACAAAUAAUCUAAAGGAAUCUCUUUGUAGUUUAUCUAAUUAUCUAAUUCAUUCUUUCUAGAGAUUAAAAAUACCUUGAAGUACAGCACUAAGUUUUAUUUACCUUGCUAUUUUCUCGGCAGCUAGAAGAGAGUCUGGUAUAUUUGAAUAAUUGUAUCAAUGCCUAUGGAAUGGAUGAGUACAUUCUAAUACAAAGUACGGCAGAGGUAAACACAAGUUUCCUAUUAGUGAACUAAAUAUAUAUAAUACUUAGAGGGAUAGCAUUCUGUAGAUUAUCAUCCUUCAUUGACAUUAUAAACUAAUAGUCUCCCUUAGUAUUUGCUGCUAUAAGGUGGUAAAAGCUAGCUAACAAAGCAAAAUGAAAGGUUGUUCAUAUUAAAUAAUACUGAAAUGAUUCCAUUUUCUACAUUGCCCUCCACAGGUCCUGAAGUGGAACCAUUAAAGAAAGGGUACCUGCCACUCCAUAUCAUCUCACUUCAAGAACUUGCAUAGAACAUCUCAGUUUCUGCUUUUAUAAAAAACAUUUCUGCGUUCUACAGAGCCAAGACACAAUCUACCAUGGCCCUCCUGGGUUUGAAGAUGACAAGCACAUUUCUUUAUUCAUGUGUACUCAAUUGCCUUUCAGCAAUCUGCUGAACUGCAUACUUGCUGGUCAGUUACCUUGGCAACUCCACAGUAAAGGCUGCUUCACUUUAAGUAUAGUAUGCCAUUCACUUUGAGAAAAACAUGAUACAGAUGUAUGACACAUUCAUCAUCUAGAAAUGGAAAAUGACUAAGCCACUAUGUUUUGUUUGUAAAAAUAAUACUUCCUUUCUGUAGCAUCAGUUUAAAUUACAGGCACCCACACAACAUUUUAGAGGAGUGCCCUUUGCCUUUCCCUUUCGCAUUUGUUACUUGCAAAACAAAUAGCUCUGCAACGGAGGCAAUUUAGGCAGUAUUUACACCUAUGCUUCCUUUCAAAAACAACAAAUGACACAGAGAAUUCGAAGCUAUAGGUUCUUGUUCUAAACGUGAGCUAUAUAAAUAAAGCUGAUGGGGUCCACUCCAACACCUACAGAGGCUAUUACUAACAGUUAACACAUGUUGCAGUCACAUAUGCCCAGGCAGCACUCACAAACCAUAAGCUUAAAGCAUGUUGUUUUCCUUAAGAGCAAGUCUUGAAAAUCAAAUUUAAACACUCUAAGAAUCCACAACACUAAGAUCUAAUAAUCUCUGAAAUAUACAUGUGUACAGUGCCAUGCUAAUCAAGCCAAGGUAACAGGGUCUGGCCUCUCUGUGUAUCGCAUGGUUUUGCAAUCUUCUACGGCUGCAAAUCCAUUACCUCUGCAAACAUACGCCACUAGAUAUAAAUGAAACUGGAAAACUAUGGGUGGUUAAAUCCAUGCAAUUCUAUCACUAUUAAUGGGAAAAACAAUGAGACCAAAAGUCCAACCCGCAAGAGGUCAAAAAUAUCAUCUCCAAAUAGCAAGCAUAGCUAGAUUUACAAAGAUUAAAAACUUCUGAAGACAGGUAGUCAUAAGGAACAGAAUUUUUUAAGUAAUAAUUACAUAUCUGAGUAGAGAGAGCCAAAGGGUUAUGUAAGCAAGUAGCUGGGAUCAUUAUCUCGCUCUCCCUAAACAUAGAUCCAAUUUAUCUCAUCACCAUGUUACCAAAACCUUGUUCACAAAACUGUUAUCUGUAUGUUUCAUUCACAGGGUAUAGAAUCUGCAGCCAUUUCAACAACUCUAUAUUAUGUGACAGCAUAGAGCCCAGAAUCAAAUAACAGACCACGAAAGCAGUAGCAAAAAAAAAGGGAGCUCAUGCUAGCUAAACAAUGUCUUGUUUUCCUUUACUAAUAGUCCAGUGGAAACUCUCUCUCCAUAAUGAAAAUAUAUGGGUGUGCACGUGUGCUUAUUACAAUUACCUUCAAAGCAAGUUUGAAUGUAUUUAGUAAACAUUAAAUUUUGAAAGUACUAUGGUGGUACGCUGCCAAUGAAUCCACAGCAUAUAACUUCACAAUUCUCACAAUGAUUAUUCUUAAUGGCAUGUGCAUAAGCACAGGCACACACACAGCCCCUUCACUACAAAAAUGUCCAGAGAACACUUGCCAGUUCUUUUUCUGCAUCACCAAGAACAAUUACAUGGCUAUAAAGAUAAAAUAACAACUGAGUAUAAGACCCUGCAAGUUUGAGCUAGUUUUAAAUCUUAAAGCCAUCUGUCUUCUGAAAUCUUUGAGAAGAAAGUCAUAAAGUAUUGUCAAUAUUUAUGUCCGGGUGACUUUGAUUAGGUACCCAGUAUGUUUAGGUCUCUCUUAUAGAUGCUUUAUUAAUAAACUAAUCACUUUAAAAUGUC